AGUCUCGUCGCGAGAAGCAGCGGCCCGGGGCGACUGAGCGGACAAACGGAAGUGUAGGUUACGGUCUGAGACAUCACCGCCAAGCUGGGCAUCGGGGAGAUGGCCGAGACUGACCCCAAGACCGUGCAGGACCUCACCUCGGUGGUGCAGACACUCCUGCAGCAGAUGCAAGAUAAAUUUCAGACCAUGUCUGACCAGAUCAUUGGGAGAAUUGAUGAUAUGAGUAGUCGCAUUGAUGAUCUGGAAAAGAAUAUCGCGGACCUCAUGACACAGGCUGGGGUGGAAGAACUGGAAAGUGAAAACAAGAUACCUGCCACGCAAAAGAGUUGAAGGUUGCUAAUAAUUUAUACUGGAAUCUGGCAUUUUUCCAAGCCAAGAGAAGAUCGAAUGGCUUUUUGCAGCUAACUACUAUGUGUAGACAGGUUUUAUAUUAUAAAGUAUGCAUUCUUAUCACCUAGUAUAUAGUUAGUUUGUAGAGUGAUUUCCCCCCAGUUUCUUGAACAUGGUAUCUUCACAUCUUGGACCUUGGUCAGUUGUGCUAUUCAUUAUUAAACACUAAAACUUUGGCGGUUCUUGCAUAACAUUGUCAGAUUUUUUAGUGUAUUUCUGUGAAGUCAUUUUUUUUCUUGUCAUUCCUUUUGUAGUAGUUGCUGUUUGGAUAAAAGUUGAUGUGUGAUUUUUUAUUAAACAAAUAGUAAACCCUUCAAUUAUAGUUAGUCUUGGUGAAGUAAGAUGUUUGUAGACUUUAGAGUUCUUUAAUUCUUGGCACAACGUGACUGUUGAGCUAACACCAAAUAGUGUGUUGGCAAUACUUUUCAAAUGGCUGAAAACACCUAAAAAUUGUUCAUUCAGAAAUAUCUGUCACUGCUCUGUUGCCAAAACUCAGAAUAGAACUUAGACGUAUGUCUGAGUCCCUGAGAUCACAUGCUAAAGUCGAUGAAAAGUAACCACUGCCACUGUCUUGUGUCAGAACUUUUACAGUACAGAAAAUAACAGAAUAGCCUUCUGUAAUGAGGCGUUUGUUAGAGUUUUGCAUGAGAUUCUAAUACUUCAGUAGGACCCUACCUACGUGGUUCAUCUACAAUGGUUACCAUAAAAAAUCUGGCAGGAUUUUAAAACUCAAUCAGUCUUUCCUUUGAGCUAGUGACUUGAAAAGAAAGAGAGAAGGAAAAGAGACCAUAUUAAGUCCAUGCCAGUUGCUUGGCUAGAAUAUGAUCAACGACUUGUAGUAGACUCAAGUUUUUAAAAAACACUAUUUUACUUAAACUGUUUCUUAUCUAAAUUCUUGCAGAGUGUCAAUGUUAUCAUUGAUUAUAGAAGACAGGGAUAAUACCUUUAUCUCUGGCCACUCAAAAAUGCAGUGCCAGGAGUGCUAAACCUAGAGGCCAAUACUGAUGACCUGGAAGGUGAUCCAUAUGAUUGUCACCACAAAGUGCUUUUACACAAAAACUUGAAAAUUUGAAAAACAUGAUUUUUUUAAGUUUCUCAUCUCACCAGUCUUGGUGUUUAUAUUGCAAAUCUAUCAAAGUAAGAAAUAAUUUGUGCUGUAUACAAAUUACAUGGGGAACAUAAAGGAGUGAGAUCCUUCUGUGAUAAAAUGAAUUCACCACUCUGGUUACCCAACUACAGAACCUCCUUUGAUCAGGCCAGUAGGUUGUGAUGCAGGCUGGAGCCCCCGAAUGCCCCACACACACUGCAGCAUUGACCAGACCAUCCGAAACCUGCGUCCCUGGUGAUGUUCUCAAGCCUCGGAAGUGGCAAAUGGAAAUGAUAUGGCCGGUUGCGGUUGUAGGAGAGUUGUGACUUAGGCAGGAGUCGACCUCCUCAAGUAAUGGAACGAUUUCAAAGGCAGGCUGCCCUGACCAAAAAUAUCUGCCAUGAAUAAAGGUGCCUGAAAUCCUGCUAUGAAGCUUCCUUUGUGUCAAAAAUCUGUUUGGUUUUCAGAUGGAAAUGCAGAAAUCACAUUAGAGUAUCAACUAAAACCUCUGGACGGAUUAAGUACAAGUAGCCCAAGGCAAAGCAGGAGAGGGGGUGUUGGGGGAGGUUGCCUGCUGGAAGGGGAAGCUGAGGAGCGGGAGGAGGGCUUGCCAAGACUGGCAUUGCAGGAGACUUGUCUCAGGUGUGUUCCCAGAACUCUUGCCCCUGGAGAUGCUGCAGGAAGGAAGGGGUUAUGGUCACUUGGGUUUAGACGACAUUCUGUGAACCUCAUGAAGAAAUUAGCAUAUUAAAGACUCUGAAAGUAGAGCAGAGAACUCAGCUUUAACCUGCUCACCUGCUAGUUUUCGAGGUCUCGCUCUGUUGCCCAGGCUGGAGUGCAGUGGCACAGUCAUAGCUCACUUGGAGCCUGAAGCUCCUGGGCUCAGGCAGUCCUCCUGCCUCAGCCUCCCAAGUAGCUAAUAUUACAGGUUCGUGCCACCGCACCUGGGUCUUGCUGUGUUGCCCAGGCUGGUCUAGAACUCCUAGGCUCAAGCAGUCCUGUCUCAGCCUCCCAAAGUGCUGGGAUUACAGGCUGGAGCCACCAUGCCUGUCCAAGGGUCUUUUUUAUACUAUAUGAAGUAUUCCUUCUCCAGCUAUUCUUGUUCGUUUACCAGCCAGUGAAGAUUCUCUUGAGGGCUGAACAAUACAGAUGAGUAUGGGGGCCCUCGCACCAAGGAAAACAGCGUUACAUUUAAUUAAGUGCCCUGUCUCAAACCCCAAGGCCCCACAGCUUCUUCAUUUGGCCCCUAGUUCAUCCUGCUUUCCUUUGAGCCACAGGAUUUUAAAAUAUUUCAAUCUUAUUUUCAUAUCAAUUUUUUCUUUGUUUCACUACAAGUACAGUCAUUGUUUAACCCUAUCAGGACUAACACAAUAUUUCACGUAACUAAGAGUUAAUUUGCCCUUGUGAGUCCUUGGAAUUUAAGCCCCACACACACACACUUAGAGCACUGUUGCUAUGGGAACAUAGAGUCCUCCAAACAAAAGUGAACUUUUUCAACAUGCUGUUUGUAAAUGGAAGCCUUCCCAAGCAGACACUGUGUUCCUCUUUUAUUUUGUAUUUUGCACAUUAUAUAUUUUGAUUAGAUUAAAAUGGAGGAAUUUGCAGGAUGUGUUGUCAUAUCUAGCCCUGAAAGUUAACUGGUUACAGUUACCAAAUGUUCACAGCUAGCGCCAUUGAAAGCAUUGACUGUAAACCGCUGUACUGUGCUAAGCCUUUUGUUUGCACUGUUUGGCUUAAUCCUCACAACAACACUGAGAGGUUUUCAUUUGAUGAGUCAUAUUUAAAGAAAAGGAACCCAAGACGGGGAGUCAGGGGCACAAGGUCACAGCUGGUAAUGAUGACCCUGGAAUGUCCUCACAGCUGCACACCUGCACCGCUCACAAACACAGCUGACCGUCUCACAGCUGCACACCUGCACCGCUCACGAGCACAGCUGACCGUCUCACAGCUGCACACCUGCACUGCUCACGAACACAGCUGAUCGUCUGCCUCUUCGUGUGAGCUGAGCUCCGAAUCUCAGCUGUCCAGGCUGUCUGGAAAUCAUCAGCCCCACUGGCUGGAUCUCAAAAUUUACUUUCAAAAGGCUGAUGGAGUGUUUUCAAUUAAACAUGACCUAAAAUUAAGUAAUAAACACACUGGAUGUGAGUUUUUAUUUGGAAUUUAAACUAUUCAGAGCUGGUAGAAAAUGUGUGCUCCUGGAUCAGUGCCUUUUUUCUCCUAAAUCAGUUGAGAACAACAACAGAAACAAAUGACAUUCCUCAAACAUUUGCCCAGAGCACAACCACGGGGAAUAUGAACCACAGGUUUUCACAUUGGUUUUCCAUGCCUAUACCUGUCCUGUCUCCCACAAAAAUUAUUGCUUGAGGCCCAACCCGGGGGAUAAAAAGACACCCCCCCGCCACUCCGUGACCUAUUAGCUUACCAUCCUAUUGGAUUUCACUGUUUUUUGUUUUGUGGUGUUUUUUUUUUAUUGCAACGAAGACUUUUAAAUGGACUCAUGAAGAAGCCAUCACCUGGAAUCUUAAUCUUGCAUUAAUUUUAAGUGUCUGAUUUUAGCUGCAGCCACUUGAGAACUUUUCAAUGAAUGAAAAUGAGGGAGGGGAGAUGCAAGUCACUGCCCAAAAACAAAACCAGAGGAAUUGUGAUUGAACAUUGCACUUAUCAACCCUACAAAUUAAUAUGGAAAUAGGAAAAGGGUUUGUUUCAACAAGUCAGGAUGACAGUAUUUUAAAAAAGAAAAAAAGGCCAGCCUGGGCAAUAUACUGAGACUCCAUCUCUACAAAAAAGUAGAAAAAUUAGCCCAGAGUGUGGUGGCACACAUCUGUGCUCCCAGCUACUCAGGAGGCUGAGGUGGGAGGAUCAUUUGAGCCCAGGAAGUCGAGGUUGCAGUGAGCUGUGAUCGGACGACUCCACUCCAGCCGGGGUGACAGAGCAAGACCCUGUCUCAAAAAAAAAAAAAAAGGGCGGAUCCUAACGCUUGGUCCUCACACCUGAGGCUCUCACUAAGAGGUGGCUGGAAGCUCCUCAGACCGCUGCCUAGGGUUCGAGUGAUCCUGAAAGCUGUACAACAUCAGCCUCUGUGGGAUCCCUGAGAAUGAUGAAAUGUAAUAUGUGGCUGUCUCAUCAACAGAGCUUCAUUUUACCAAAGCAUAUGUAGACACCACAUACAUGAACUACAUACCUAUCGUGUAGAUGCUGCCCUGCCUCAUAAGAACACUCUUGACUGUCCUGCUUCACAAUAAUAAUCUUCGCAAUAAUGAUCUAAUAAUGGUCAAAUUCUGUGUCUCUACCGUAGAAAACAGAAUUUGACCAUUUAGUCACGUUGGUCUUGCAAAAUGUCCACCUUCCAAAAGAGAACAGUAUUGCUUCCCAAUAAUUAAGAAUAGUCUGGAUUCAGGAUCCAGCAGCUUAGAAGCGUUUAGCUACCAAUAGCAAAAAUCAGCCCUUUUAACAAUGGUGGGAUGUAUUAUUUCACAUGGCAAGAAGUCCCAAGGGAGGGCAGCUCUGGGGCGAGUAAAUUCUGCACCUCAGUAAAACUAAGAGCAAGACCCGGCCGGGCGCAGUGGCUCAUGCCUGUAAUCCCAGCACUUUGGGAGGCCGAGGUGGGUGGAUCACCUGAGGUCAGGAGUUCUAAACCAGCCUGGCCAACAUGGCGAAACCCCCGUCUCUACUAAAAAUACAAAAAUUAGCCAGGCGUGGUGGUGGGCGCUUGUAAUCCCAGUUGCUCGGGAGGCUGAGGGAGGAGGAUCGCUUGAACUCAGGAGGUGGAAGUUGCAGUGAGCCGAGAUCGUGCCACUGCACUCCAGCCUGGGUAACAGAGCGAGACUCCAUCUCAAAAAAUAAAAAACAAAAAAAUAAAUAAAAAAUAAAAAGACCCAACCCCAGAUUUGUUCCACCUGGGUGCAUCCGGUCAGAGAAUGCCUUUCUUCUUCCCUUUUGUCUCCUAAGAGUGAAGAAAAUGUUUCUUUGAAGGUGUUUCCACCCCACUCCUGUGCCUAAAAUGAUCCUGGCAAACAGGACCCGCAUGAUAGGUUGAGCCAUGUGGUUCUUGUUUUUUUGUUGUCACAACUCAGGUUGGGGGUGUUACUGGCAUCAAGAGUGUAGAAACCAGGGAUGCUGCGUCAACACCCUACCAUGCACAGGACAACCCUCACCCCAAAGAGUGGCACAGCCCCAAGUGUCAACAGUGCUGAGGUUGAGGAAUCCCAGCUUAACCCAUUCAUGAGACCACCUGAGCCUGGUGUAACGGUUCUGCUGAUAGUUUCCGGACCCUCAGAGGUGGAGACAUAAGAGAACAAUACCAGGGUUCCAUCAGAAAGGAAAUCAGAAUGGCUAUCGGGUGGACAACCUACAGUGUUUGCUACAGACCUUCUAGAUGUAACUUCUAGAUUAUAAACACUGGUAACACUGGAGAUGGUUAAAUCGGAAUUAGCUGACUGUCAACCUUGGUGGCACAUUAGAAUCACCUGGGGAGCAGUUCAAAGGCCCAAAACUGGGCAGCACCACAGAACCCUCACAUCAGAAUCCCCAUGGGUGGGCCCAGACAGCAGUGUUCAUCUUAGACUCCAGUGUGCAGUCGAGGUCGAGAACUGCAUUCAAGAAGGCCUGUCUACUGCGAACCGUCCGAUGAUGUAAUUCACCAAGUUCCAUGGGAUUCCGCCACGCCCGUGUCAACCCAGCUGACACGUCCAACUUGGACAAUCAGGGCUUUGACCCCCGUUACCUGGCAUUCAAUUCAAUCCAUGUGUCACGCAUGCCCCAACAAUUUGUGUCCCAACUGUUUGAAUCAAAGGAUUUCUGAUUCCCUGAUGGGUGAUGACUCAGUAACCGGAUUCAGCUUCAGAUCUGCCUGACAUUUUUCCUGCCUGUCCUGGGCCAGGUAUGGCGCUAGCUGCUUUCACCUGUAUCAUCUCAUUCACUGCUCAGAGGCUCUCGAAAGCUGUUGACAUUAUCAAAAAGUUUUCCAGCUGGAAUUCAUCUCCCUCUAAUCAGCCUUCAAAACCUCCAUUUGUAAACCAUUGCUGUAGUUUUAUUACCUCUUACCUUGGUCUUUACAAGUUGCUGUCAAAACCCAGUAAGUGUUUACAGAAAGAAACUUUACAUAUUAAAUAUCUUAAAGGUCUUUUAUGCAGAAUAUGCAGUUAAUUUUGAUGGGCUAUGGAUAAUCAUCAGAAGAGCCAUUUCUGGAAAUGUAAAUAAUAUGGCUGUUUCUUUUAACAGUGCAUUCUCCUGAAAACAUAAGACCAUUUGACUGAUUCUGCUCCAGAAUCUUAUUGAGGCAAAGGACUGGACCGAAUUAUUCAUGGAACAGAAGCCUAGGACUGGUAAGUCCAGGAAAUGCUGCAAAACAAUGCCCUCAAAAGAAAUCAGCCUUUCCCUUUGAUAGGUAUCUCUCCUGCAAGCCAGGCUCAGGUGCGCCUCAAUUAGAACCUGUGUUCGCUGGGGCCAUAAUUAAGAAUCUUAAAGGGAAAGAAUGUUUUGAAAGCCAUCUGUCAAAAGUACGCAGUCUUGCUUGUAGAAUUUUAGAGGUUCAUGGUUACCGUGGGUCGGCACUGGGUCUGUGAGCCCUCAUCCCCAGGGCUCGGUUUCCUAUCAGAAUCCUUGUCUGGAAGGUUGAUUAUAUCAGAUGCGCAUUUUGCCAGCAUCCUCAGAAGGAGAUGCGAGGAAGAUUCUUUUCCUGGGCCACUCUCAUUUUCUCAAACUUGGACAAGUCUUAACAAUAAUCUGUGACCCAACUUUGUCUUCCCCAUGAUGAAAAACAGACCCCAUAGAAACUCUCUGGCACAAAAACUCUGGAAUCACUGACCCCAGACAUUGUUCCCUGCCAUCCACUCUGCCAGACAUUUCUUGGAUUUAUUCAAGCUGACUUGUAUUCCAGAACAAUUGUGGACAAGAUUUGCUAGUAAUGCUUCCAACAAGUUACCGUUUAGCAAGUUCAGAACUUGAAGAAUCCCUUUUAUCCUAACGCUGACUAAUAAACUGGUGAGAACUGUUUGAAAUACCCAUAAGUCAAUGGAGGUCGUAAUUUGCUUUUAUGCUGUAUUAAACACCACUGAGAUGUUAAGGUCUUUCUUGGGAACCACCGUGAUGUUCUCUUCUGGACUCUUCGUAACCCCUUCAGCAGACGACCCUGUAUCUGGUCUUGGUUCUGAAAGGUUUGCAGCGGCACCUAAGUCACUGAAGUUCUGGCAGAAUUCAUUCUCCUGCUCUCUACUGGGACUUGUUUUCCAUAAUUGGUCUGAGAACAACAGAUUUUUUUCUUUUUUGCCUCGGAUUUCAACAAAACAUACAUGGAAAGAAUAUUUUCUUCCUUGGAGACAUUUCCCAUAGGGCAGUGGUUCUUAAAAUACGUUCCUGAACCGGCAGCAUCAGAAUCCCCUGGGAACGUGCUGGAAAUGUAGAUCCCCAGGCCCUACCUAGCCCUACUGAAUCAGAGACCCUGGGAGGGAGGUCCAGCAGCCUGGGUUUUAACACAUCCUCCAGGCGAUUCUGAGAGUGAGAGAGCCAGGGCCUUCGGGCAUCAACCUUGGGGCGAGGGUGUUGGGUUGCCCAACACCCUUUAGUCUAAUGGCUUUAGGGUCAAAUAUGUCUAAACCAAGAAGCCCCAUGGGGCACUGAUUAGCAUGCAGGUCCCCAGGCCCCCUUUUUGUAGAUCCUGAUUCAGAAUAUCUGGGACGGGGGCUGGAGAUUCAUAUUUUUAAUAAAUUCCCUCAUUUAUUAUUUUUGUGUCUUAUUUCCCAUACACAAAAACACUGCGUAGAGAAAUGGGAGUGUGGGCGAUGCUCCCAUGCUGGGAGUCUCAGGCCUGGGCUAGUCCUAAAAUAAUUGAAAAGGAAUUGAUUCUUAAUUACCCAGAACGUCCACGCUCUAGGACCUAGUGUGACCUCUUCUGCCUUCUGAACCGAGGAGUCCACCCCUAAGCCCGAGGAACUGAGCGUGAAGAGCCCUGACGCCAUGAAGACUUGAAUCACUUUAAAGCAAUUUGCUUCUUAUUAAAAUGUACUUCAGUAAAAAAUCAUUUCAACUCUUAAGCCACAAAAGGAUAUCCAAUCAUUUAAAGCUUCCUGAGUGUUUCGGUUGAUUAAAAAGCUUUUAAAGAGCAUAGUAAAUAUUUUACCAGAAGGAUAAGUUAUUCAGUAUGGAGAUUAUUUAUUAAAAACUAGUAAUUUAUU